ACUCCAUGCCGGGUCUCUAGUUCCAGCGCGCCUCGGCUCGCUCGCGCGGCGGGAGAGUUGGCGCAAACCUCGCGGCAGCCGCAGCCUCCUCGCGCGCCUCUCCUUCCCCUACGCCCUCCGCUCCCGCCAUGGGGCCAACGUGGGGCUCCUAAGAGUUGCCGGCUCUCAGCGGCGCAAUCUCCAGCCAAAGUCACCGCGGGCGGACUAUGGCUUAGGGCGCCAGAGGGGUUAGAGGUACGGGAAGAGGAAAAGACGGCUAACUGGGAAAAAAAGAGAAAACGAAAGAAAAGCCAAACGAUGAGUUUCCACAAGGAGGACGGAGUGAACAGUCUGUGCCAGAAGGCUCUGCACAUCGUCACCGAGCUGUGCUUCGCCGGCCAGGUGGAGUGGGAGAAGUGCUCGGGCAUCUUCCCUCGGGACAGGGGCAGCCAGGGCGGAAGCAGCACAGAUAUUUCAGUCAGCCUGUUAGCUGUCGUUGUCAGCUUUUGUGGACUGGCCUUGUUGGUUGUCUCACUUUUUGUCUUCUGGAAGCUGUGUUGGCCAUGCUGGAAAAGCAAACCUGUGACUUCCAACAUCACUACGCUUCCACAGAGCAUUUCAAGUGCUCCUACUGAAGUUUUUGAGACUGAAGAGAAAAAAGAAAUUAAGGAAAAUGAAAAGCCAGCCGUAAAAGCUAUUGAGCCUGCAAUAAAAAUCAGCCACACUUCCCCUGACAUCCCAGCAGAAGUCCAAACUGCUUUAAAAGAACAUUUAAUUAAACAUGCACGUGUGCAAAGACAAAUUACUGAGCCUACGUCAUCAACCCGCCACAGUUCCUUCCGAAGACACCUGCCGAGGCAAAUGCAGGUUUCCAGUGUUGAUUUUAGCAUGGGCACAGAACCUGUUUUACAACGAGGAGAAACAACAACCAGCAUUGGGAGGAUAAAGCCAGAACUCUACAAACAGAAAUCAGUUGACUCUGAGGGCAACCAAAACGAAGAUGUCAAAAUCUGUGGGAAACUUAACUUUACCCUCCAGUAUGAUUAUGAAAAUGAACUUCUAGUUGUUAAAAUUAUCAAAGCUUUAGAUCUCCCUGCUAAAGACUUCACAGGAACUUCUGACCCUUAUGUGAAGAUGUAUCUUCUUCCAGAUAGGAAAAAGAAAUUUCAGACCCGCGUGCACAGAAAGACUUUAAAUCCUCUAUUUGAUGAAACUUUUCAAUUUCCUGUAGCAUAUGAUCAACUAAGCAACCGAAAACUACAUUUCAGUGUGUAUGAUUUUGACAGAUUUUCUAGACAUGACAUGAUUGGGGAAGUGAUUCUUGAUAAUUUGUUUGAAGUCUCUGAUCUCUCCAGGGAAGCCACAGUAUGGAAAGAUAUUCACUGUGCUACCACAGAAAGUAUAGACCUGGGUGAAAUCAUGUUUUCCCUUUGUUACCUACCGACGGCUGGGCGUAUGACAUUGACAGUCAUUAAGUGCAGAAAUCUGAAGGCGAUGGAUAUUACUGGCUCAUCAGAUCCUUAUGUCAAAGUGUCCCUGAUGUGUGAAGGUCGAAGAUUAAAAAAGAGGAAAACAACUACAAAGAAAAACACUCUAAACCCUGUGUACAAUGAGGCCAUUAUUUUUGACAUCCCUCCAGAGAACGUGGACCAGGUCAGCCUCUCCAUUGCGGUCAUGGAUUACGAUAGGGUAGGACACAAUGAGGUCAUAGGAGUGUGCAGAACAGGACUGGAUGCUGAGGGUCUUGGGCGAGACCACUGGAAUGAAAUGCUGGCCUAUCAUCGAAAACCAAUAACGCACUGGCACCCAUUGCUGGAGUUACCUGGCCGGGCGACCAGUUUUGAUAGUCAAGGAUCCUGCCCUUCUCCUAAACCACCUUCCACACCAUAAUGCCUCCAAAAUGAGACCAUGAUAUUAAGCAUCUAGGAUCACGUGCUCAUUGAAUCAGAAAAAAAGUGGAAGGUUUGGUUUCCUCAUUUGAAAUAUAUCCGUACUAAUGAACAAACUUGAUGUGCACUUUUUUAUUUGCUUUUAUUGUUGAUUUUUUAACUUUGAACAUCAAUACAUUUUACUUGAAUACAUAUAGUCCUUAGUUGCAUAAGGCAUUUUAUCCUUCGUAUCAAAUGCCUGUUAGCACAAAGAGUGUUUUACUAUGUUGUAAUUCUUUGCAUAUGAAAUGUUUUUUUAAACAGUUCAUACUUACCUAAAAUUAAAUAUAGUUUAUGCUGCUAUUGUAUAAAGUAGCACAUGUCAUAUAUGUAUGGGUUUGAUUUUGUUAUACUGUGUUCAUUUCUAGUUGUGCAGGUGGUUCUGUAUAAACUUAAAAGGAGAUUUUGAACUUAACUUACACAACAUUAAAUCCUUGCACAAUCAAAUUAAUGUUACUUAUCUGAUAAUACUUUUCUUUCAUUCUCAGAAAAUUACUUUCUUGGUGAGGUUUGGCUCUGCUAAACUCAAAACUUGUCUCUCAAGCUUGUUCUUUAAAAUACAUAGACAAAGCUGUAAAUUUAAAGAAUCAUUUUGAAUAUAAAUUUAAGAAGUAAUACUUAUUGGCUGAAAAACGGAGGCUGAGCCAUUGUGGCUACCAUUUUACACUGUUUUACUGUAACAUUAGCUCAAAUAUCUGUUGCACUGUUCAACUGAUAUUUUUAAAAUUCUAAUAAUCUUCAUCUCAAAUGUAGCAUUAGUAUUUCUAAGUGAACAGAAUCAGAAGUUAAUUUUUAAGUGUUUGUAAGGUUCUCAAGUACUGUGACAUGUAUUUUUUUGUGACGUGUAUUUUUUGUGACUUGAAGCUAUCAUAUAGAUCCUGUAUUUCUGAUAGACCAUACUAACAGACACCAAAGGAACAACAACACUGUCUGUGUUCAUCACCGUUUAGAUUGUACACAGUAAUGGUGACUCUUAAACCCAGUCAGAAGCUCAUCAUUGGAAUUCAGUAUUUUCUUAAAGAAAGGAUGAUUUAUUUUCAGCAACAUAUAGAAAUAUACUAUAAAUAUUAAUAAUACAACUUCAAUGCUUAAUAAUAAUAAACAAAUUAAUUCUAAAGGCCCAGGCCUCCAGUCCUUGCAUGAAAGGCAUUUGCCUUCAUAAGGAUCAAGGUUCAGGCCACUACAUGUAAAAACUAUGCAAGUGUUUUUACAAGACAGAACUUUCUUUUAAGUCAGGUCAACAUAUUUUGUCCCAUUUUCAGGCCCUGUUGGAAGGUAUCUAUACUGAAUUACCCCAACCUUACUUUUAAGAUGUGUGGUAUAGAUAGUAUAUAUUUCAAGCUUAUUUCAAAAUUGGUGGUUUUUUUAAAAAAAGAGGCAAGAAAAUAAAAACAUAUUUACCUGGAUGAGAAAAUUUUAUCAGCGGUUAUGAAAUUUUUAUUUUUGUAAAAUCCCAUUAUUUCUAAAUAUUAAAAAAAAGUUUUAAAAGCCUUGAAAUUUUGUUGACAUCUCUUAUAGUGAUGGCAUUACUGUUAAUUAAGAGGUAAAUAUUUUGCACAUUACCAUUUUAAAGGCAAACACAGUUCUGCCUCAGAUUUUUCAAAAAUGCUUAUACCACCCUAAGGAAAACAGGUACUCCUAGCUAACAUUUUCUCAUUGAAAAUAAUAGAAGAAAGCUGUUUGGAAACAUUUGGCUACCUUGUCGAGCCUAAAAGAAUUAUUUGCUAUAGGUAAAAUGAAAGAUGACACUUGCAUUUUGAAAUUAUUUGUUUUAUUGGGAAAUAAAACUUUUCAAAUAGGAAGACAAAAAGUUAUACUAUUAAUAGAAUGACAUUUUUGGAGACAGUUGUUUUAUUAGUAGAUAUAACUGCAGCUUAAAGUAAAUUAGCAAUUACGUUUCCUAAGUGAGUAUAAUUAUUUUCACCCAAAAACACAUUUUUAAGGACUUUUUGUUGAUUCUUAGAAACUCGCUUUUCUUUACUCCCUAAGGAGAAAAAGCCAAUGCUUGUGAUGAAAAAAUGUGAACCAUUGGCCAAUCAGAAGACUCUAAUAUGGGAAUUGUAGAUUAAAAUAAGUUUUAAAAGAAUUUUUUAAAUGUUUCCUUGAAGUUAGAAUAAACUCAUCAUGCAAGGAUAUGUGUUAAUCCUGAGAAAGAGAUCAGCGAGAGGAAAUUCACCACAACUCAUCUUUCAUGUAAUUCAGGAGGUAGGUUUAUGCUCAGAUUAAUAAGGCAUGAUUGUUAAAAAUGACAGUUCAUAUUAUUAAAAUGUAAUCCUAACAAUUUUAAUACAACACACCCUCACUCUACACAGCCCACACAUUCAUAUACACAUAACUUACCAUCUUUCUGCUUGUAAUUGAAGAUGAAAUAUUUUCAGUUUCAGUAUUUAAAAUAAGAUUUGAUAUUACAAAUCCCCUUAUUUGUGUGGGACAUCACAUUUUAAUGACAGUACUGACACAUUAUGAAGCUGCAGUUCAGGUAUAUAAUGAACAUCUAAUUUCAGGGACUUCUUCAGGGACUUACCAAAUAUCAGUCUAGGAAAAAAAAGAGUAA